AGAGGCGGGUGCCGCGCUGUCGCCCAGGUAUCUGGGGUCUCUGGUGUCUGAGUGUCUCAUUGUCGGCGCGAACACAAUUGCUCCAGCCACAGGCGAGGCCUGGCCAAGGUGUGGGCGCAUCUGGGGCAGGUCUUGAGAGGUCCAGCGCCCGGUGGUGCGGACAGAGGCGGGGCACCGCGGCGCUCGCCGCCGCCUCCCCGCAGGUGAUCAUCCUCCUGCAGGUGUCCUCGGGUCUCAGGUGGCUGCGUGUCUGCGCCAUGGUUGACAUUCUGGGCGAGCGGCACCUGGUGACCUGUAAGGGCGCGACGGUGGAGGCCGAGGCGGCGCUGCAGAACAAGGUGGUGGCACUGUACUUCGCGGCGGCCCGGUGCGCGCCGAGCCGCGACUUCACGCCGCUGCUCUGCGACUUCUAUACGGCGCUGGUGGCCGAGGCGCGGCGGCCCGCGCCCUUCGAAGUGGUCUUCGUGUCAGCCGACGGCAGCUCCCAGGAGAUGCUGGACUUCAUGCGCGAGCUGCAUGGCGCCUGGCUGGCGCUGCCCUUCCACGACCCCUACCGGCAACGGAGUCUCGCUCUGUUGCCCAGGCUGGAGUGCAGUGGCGUGAUCUUAGCUCACUGCAACCUUUGCCUCCUGGGUUCAAGUGAUUCUCUAGCCUUAGCCUCCUGAGCAUCUGGGACUACAGCCAUUGCUGUGAAUUACGUGAGGGAAAGAUAUUGAAGAGGAGUUGGACACUCCGAGAGUGCAGCUGUUCUCCCCCCGCACCAUCCGUGUCCUGCAUUCUGCGAGUCUGUGCUCAUUAACAAUGUGCUGUGACCAUGUGACUCAGCAAUCCUGCUGCUGGGUAUAUACCCGAAAGAAAGGAAAAGGAAGCCAGUAUAUUGAAGAGGUAUCUGCACCCCCAUGUUUAUUGCAGCACUGUUCACAACAGCCAAGAUUUGGAAGCAACCUAAGUGUCCAUCAACAGAUGAAUGGAUAAAGAAAACGUGGUACAUAUACACAAUGGAGUACUCUUCAGCCAUUAAAAAAAUGAGAUUCUGUCAUUUGCAAUAAUAUAGAUGGAAAAGGAGGCCCUUAUGUGAAGUGAAAUAAGCCAGGCACAGAAAGACAAACAUCACAUGUUCUCACUUAUUUGUGGGAUCUAAUGAUCAAAACAAUUGAACUCUUGGACAUAGAGAGUAGAAGGUUGGUUACCAGAAGCUGGAAAGGAAAGUGGGGUUGGGAGGAAGGUGGGAAUGGUUAAUAGGUACAAAAAAAUACAAAGAAUAAAUAAGACCUAAUAUUUGAUAGCACAACAGUGUGACUACUGUCAAUAAUCAUUUAAUUGUACAUUUAAAAAUAACUAUAAUUGCAUUGUUUGUAACACAAAAGAUAAAUGCUUGAGGGGAUGAA